GCCUCAGCCGCCUCAGCCGCGGUCGCCGCCGCUUCGGCUGACUUAGGCUCCGCCGCCGCCUCCUCACCCGCCUCGCCCCGACCCCGCCCGGGCCUCCCGGCCUCUCCCCGCCGGCCCGCGGGCUCGCCGUCCGGCGCAGGGCAGCACAUUGGAGAUAUAUUUCCACAGCAUCUGGCUUUUCUUGUUCCUGUUCUGAAGUAAAUGUAACUGCUAUCCUCUGGAGGACUGUCUACAAGAGAGAAGCUCCCCACGUGGUUCCGUCUUCAGAAGGGAGGAAAACACAGAAGACGAGGGCUGAAAGAUGGCAUUGGACUUGGCACAGGGAUGGUCAGGAGGUCCUGAGUCACUUUGAGAAGGUCGGUAGGCUCCACGACAAAAGUCAACCCUUCUGUAAAUCACCUGCUGUGGUUAUGAUGCUCUGAGUUCAAUACGUCUGAACCUUUGCUGUCUAUGGAUCUGCUCUAAACCUUAUAGCCUGCUUAUGGGGGAAGGUGACGCCUUCUGGGCCCCAUCUGUCCUUCCUCACAGCACCCUCAGCACCUUAAGCCACCACCCUCAGCCACAAUUUGGCAGAAGGAUGGAGUCCAAGGUCUCAGAAGGUGGCCUGAAUGUGACCCUCACCAUCCGCCUGCUGAUGCAUGGAAAGGAAGUUGGAAGCAUCAUCGGGAAGAAAGGAGAAACUGUGAAGAAGAUGCGUGAGGAGAGUGGUGCAAGGAUCAACAUCUCAGAGGGAAACUGCCCAGAGAGGAUUGUGACCAUCACAGGCCCCACAGACGCCAUCUUCAAGGCCUUUGCCAUGAUCGCAUACAAGUUUGAGGAGGAUAUCAUCAACUCCAUGAGCAACAGCCCUGCCACCAGCAAGCCCCCAGUGACGCUGAGGCUGGUGGUGCCUGCCAGCCAGUGUGGGUCCCUGAUCGGCAAAGGAGGCUCCAAGAUCAAGGAGAUCAGGGAGUCCACAGGUGCCCAGGUGCAGGUGGCUGGGGACAUGCUGCCCAACUCCACGGAGCGAGCGGUGACCAUCUCGGGGACCCCAGAUGCCAUCAUCCAGUGCGUCAAGCAGAUCUGUGUGGUCAUGCUGGAGUCCCCACCGAAAGGUGCCACCAUUCCCUACCGCCCAAAGCCCGCCUCCACCCCUGUCAUUUUUGCAGGUGGUCAGGCCUACACAAUCCAGGGACAGUAUGCCAUCCCUCACCCGGAUCAGUUGACCAAGCUCCACCAGUUGGCCAUGCAGCAAACCCCCUUUCCUCCCCUCGGACAGACCAACCCCGCUUUCCCCGGAGAAAAGCUGCCUUUACACUCCUCCGAAGAAGCUCAAAAUCUGAUGGGCCAGUCAUCAGGACUACAAGCAAACCCUUAAGGAGGAAGAUCAGUCUGUGCUGGAUUUGCCUGCACCCCUCCCGACUUGCAUUAAAAUGUUCAUUCCUCAGAUACUGUGGGGUAGCACAUAGAUUUGUAGAUUCAGUGACCAAGGCCAUGAAACAGACACAGUUGUUUGCCUGGGGCUUAGCAGGUUCCUAGGUGCCCGUGAAGAAGAUGCCACACACGCACCACACCUUGUGGCUCCAUGUGCACAUGGCCGGUGCCACAGUGGCUUCCUGGUGGCCAGGCAGGUGUCCUGUAAUGACCCUCCCCUCACCAAGGCCCUGAGGACUGCAGUGCACACACAUGCCAGCCACAGCAGGGUUAAAUUGGGUGGGCAGCGAUGGGAGGUGUUUGUGGCCUCUUUGAAUGCUGCGGCCAGGAGACUUCCAGCGUGGGCUUGGACUGCAGGUUGGGGCAGCCUCCUUUACCCCUGGUACCUGGAAUGUCGUCAUCUUCAUAAGAAACAGACUCACCUGGGCCGUGCUGUCCUGAGAUGAGUGAACACGUCGGCCAUGCCGUCCUGAGAUGAACAAACACGUCGGCCAUGCUGUCCUGAGAUGAACAAACACGUCGGCCGUGCCGUCCUGAAAUGAAUGAACACAUCAGCCAUGCUGUCCUGAAAUGAAUGAACACAUCGGCCAUGCUGUCCUGAGAUGAAUGAACACCUGGGCCAUGCCGUCCUGAAAUGAAUGAACACGUCGGCCAUGCCGUCCUGAGAUGAAUGAACACAUCGGCCAUGCUGUCCUGAGAUGAACAAACACCCGGGCCAUGCUGUCCUGAGAUGAACGAACACCCGGGCCAUGCUGUCCUGAGAUGAACGAACACCUGGGCCAUGCUGUCCCGAGAUGAAUGAACAUGUCGGCCGUGCCGUCCUGAGAUGAAUGAACACAACGGUCAUGCUGUCCUGAGAUGAAUGAACACCUGGGCCAUGCCAUCCUGAAAUGAAUGAACACAUUGGCCAUGCUGUCCUGAGGUGGAUGAACACCUAGUCCAUGCCAUCCUGAGAUGAAUGAACACAUCAGCCAUGCCGUCCCGAGAUGAAUGAACACAUCGGCCAUGCUGUCCUGAGAUGAACGAACACCUGGGCCUUGCCGUCCUGAGAUGGAUGGACACCUGGUCCAUGCCGUCAUGAGAUGAAUAAACACAUCAGCCAAGCUAUCCUGAGAUGAAUGAACACAUCAGCCAUGCUGUCCUGAGAUGAGUGAACACCUGGUCCAUGCCAUCCUGAGAUGAAUGAACACAUCGGCCAUGCCGUCCUGAGAUGAAUGAACACAUCGGCCAUGCUGUCCUGAGAUGAACAAACACCUGGGCCAUGCUGUCCUGAGAUGAACGAACACCUGGGCCAUGCCGUCCUGAGAUGAACGAACACGUCGGCCAUGCCGUCCUGAGAUGAACGAACACCCGGGCCAUGCUGUCCUGAGAUGAACGAACACCUGGGCCAUGCUGUCCCGAGAUGAAUGAACACGUCGGCCGUGCCGUCCUGAGAUGAAUGAACACAACAGUCAUGCUGUCCUGAGAUGAAUGAACACCUGGGCCAUGCCAUCCUGAAAUGAAUGAACACAUUGGCCAUGCUGUCCUGAGGUGGAUGAACACCUGGUCCAUGCCAUCCUGAGAUGAAUGAACACAUCAGCCAUGCCGUCCCGAGAUGAAUGAACACAUCGGCCAUGCUGUCCUGAGAUGAACGAACACCUGGGCCUUGCCGUCCUGAGAUGGAUGGACACCUGGUCCAUGCCGUCAUGAGAUGAAUAAACACAUCAGCCAAGCUAUCCUGAGAUGAAUGAACACAUCAGCCAUGCUGUCCUGAGAUGAGUGAACACCUGGGCCAUGCCGUUCUGAGAUGAAUGAACACAUCGGCCAUGCUGUCUUGAGAUGAAUGAACACAUCAGCCAUGCCGUUCUGAGAUGAAUGAACACAUCGGCCACGCCGUCUUGAGAUGAAUGAACACAUCGGCCAUGCCAUCCUGAGAUGAAUGAACACAUUGGCCAUGCUGUCUUGAGAUGAAUGAACACCUGGGCCAUGCUGUCUUGAGAUGAAUGAACACCUGGGCCAUGCUGUCCUGAGACGAAUGAACACCUGGGCCAUGCUGUCUUGAGAUGAAUGAACACAUCAGCCAUGCUCUCCUGAGAGGGAUGAACACCUGGGCCUUGCCGUCCUGAGAUGAAUGAACACAUUGACCAUGCUGUCCUGAGAUGAUUGUCCUGGUUAUGCAGACAUUUCUUUAUAUUAUUUGCUUAACUUUAAUGCCCUCCUAGGAAGAUUUCCCAUACUUUCCUCCCUUCAAUCAAAAUAUCCCAAGUUCAACAGGUCUGGCUCACUCCUCUCUAUUCAUCUAAGGUCUACUUUGUUCAGGAAUUUCUGUCUAGGACUCAGGCAGGACCAAGGAAAUCUUUUCAGUGACAUUUUAAAUAUCACUGUUUAUGGAAUGUGUAUAGAUAACUGAAUAACCAAAUAAGUGUUGUUUUGAAAGUAUCUUUAUUAAAAGAAUAUAAAGAACAGAAA